AGAACAGAGCGAGGCUCCUGGCGCACUAGGGACUCCAGGAGGCAGCUCCGCCAGAGACGCGGGUCGUGCUUCGGGAAACCGGGGGGCGGGGGGAGGGGAAGAGCGCAGAAAAGAAAACCCACCAAGGCGGGGACUGGCCUGAGCGGGGAGGGGCGGCGAGGCCGGAGCCCCUCUCUGUUGGGCGGACUCCCCAUGGCCAGAGGCUGAGCUCCACUCCCGCCGGCCGCUCCCUAGGGGAAGGGGAAGGAGAGGGGAGAGCAGCGACAGGCCUCCAGCAAGCAAGCGCGGGCGGCAUCCGCAGUCUCCAGAAGUUUGAGACUUGGCCGUAAGCGGACUCGUGCGCCCCAACUCUUUGCCGCGCCAGCGCCUGGAGCGGAGAGCAGAGGCGGCCCGGCCGCGGCGCGCCGGCUUUGUCAUGAUGGCCAGCUACCCCGAGCCCGAGGACGCGGCGGGGGCCCUGCUGGCCCCAGAGACCGGUCGCACAGUCAAGGAGCCAGAAGGGCCGCCGCCGAGCCCAGGCAAGGGCGGUGGGGGUGGCGGCGGGACAGCCCCGGAGAAGCCGGACCCGGCGCAGAAGCCCCCGUACUCGUACGUGGCGCUCAUCGCCAUGGCGAUCCGCGAGAGCGCGGAGAAGAGGCUCACGCUGUCCGGCAUCUACCAGUACAUCAUCGCGAAGUUCCCGUUCUACGAGAAGAAUAAGAAGGGCUGGCAAAAUAGCAUCCGCCACAACCUCAGCCUCAACGAGUGCUUCAUCAAGGUGCCGCGCGAGGGCGGCGGCGAGCGCAAGGGCAACUACUGGACGCUGGACCCGGCCUGCGAAGACAUGUUCGAGAAGGGCAACUACCGGCGCCGCCGCCGCAUGAAGAGGCCCUUCCGGCCGCCGCCCGCGCACUUCCAGCCCGGCAAGGGGCUCUUCGGGGCCGGAGGCGCCGCAGGCGGGUGCGGCGUGGCGGGCGCCGGGGCCGACGGCUACGGCUACCUGGCGCCCCCCAAGUACCUGCAGUCUGGCUUCCUCAACAACUCGUGGCCGCUACCGCAGCCUCCCUCACCCAUGCCCUAUGCCUCCUGCCAGAUGGCGGCAGCCGCAGCGGCUGCAGCAGCUGCGGCUGCAGCCGCGGGCCCCGGUAGCCCUGGCGCGGCCGCUGUGGUCAAGGGGCUGGCGGGCCCGGCCGCCUCGUACGGGCCGUACACACGCGUGCAGAGCAUGGCGCUGCCCCCCGGCGUAGUGAACUCGUACAAUGGCCUGGGAGGCCCGCCGGCCGCACCCCCGCCUCCGCCGCACCCCCACCCGCAUCCGCACGCACACCAUCUGCACGCGGCCGCCGCACCGCCGCCUGCCCCACCGCACCACGGGGCCGCCGCGCCGCCGCCGGGCCAGCUCAGCCCUGCCAGCCCAGCCACCGCCGCGCCCCCGGCGCCCGCGCCCACCAGUGCGCCGGGCCUGCAGUUCGCUUGUGCCCGGCAGCCCGAGCUCGCCAUGAUGCAUUGCUCUUACUGGGACCACGACAGCAAGACCGGCGCGCUGCAUUCGCGCCUCGAUCUCUGAGAGCCCACCGCAUGCCGGUGCAGACGGAUGCGAGGAUGCAGGGACGCGCGACGCCGGCCCCGGUCGCAGCCGACGACGCCGCCGCCAGCCUGACCUCACACCCUCUGGGCCCGCCUCUGGAGCCAGCGCCCAGGGUCCCUCUGUGCUUUUUCGCUUUCCUAAGCUCCUGUCGCUCCUCUUUGUCCCCUCAGUUUAUGUCCUCCUGUGCUCACCUCCCUGACCUCUGUGACCUUGCACUCCCCUGGCCUGAAGCUGCCUCUCUGCGCGCUUUCUACUGGGCUCGUCUCUUUCCGGAGCCCCAGCGUCUCCUGCCCAAAUUCACCGCGGAAAGGGCCCGGGGCGGAGGUGCGACCGGGCGUCGGCAGCGCAGACCUCUUGGCCUUCUCUCACAGGUCGGUGCGCUCGCUCUCCGCGUUCCCCGCCCGACUGCCGUGCAGUCCAUGGCUAGACGCGCCGGACAGGACUGAUGGCGGGACCGCGCUGCCCGAGAAAGGGACGGACCAAUACGUGUGUUUGCUCCGCGAACCCUCUUGAAGCUGUUCAGAAGCCGCUUGCCGCGGGGCCCACUAGGCGGGGCGGGGGUUGGGACCCAGCGGGAGCCGGGGCAGCCUGGCUCCACGGCCUGUACUCGGUUUACACCGCGGGCGGGCGCGGAGGGAGGCUGCGUUUCCUCCGCUAUCAGUCCCGUCGCUUCGGGCACCUCCGGGCCCCGGCGGCUGGCUAAUGUUUUGUUUGAAAGAUCGGUGGAACUUUUUAAGAGAGUAUUUAAAAAAAAAAAAAGGAAAAAAAAUUCACCGGGCAACCGGGGAAGUAUUGUGGCCUUGGAGUUUGCUAAAUCCAAAUAUGAAAAUCAAAAGCUUUAGUAUUCCUCAUCUUCUCUUCUGGAAGAUUUGCGUUAGAGUUUUUGUUGGGCCUUCAAAAAGCUGUGUUCAGAGUUAGGAGAAUAUAUCCAAUAAAAGAUGGUUUCGUCUACCAAUUGGGGAAGUUUCACCCUCUCCCUAUCUGAAGAAAAAAAUCAAAAACAAAUGUCCCCGGAUCUUUCGAUGCAAGUCCUGGAGGCAGGGAGAUCACUGCCUGCCUGGCCCACGCUGCUGGGACGGCUCGUCCUCCCUGCUUUUUGUUUUUCAAACCUCCUGCUUCUCCCACCUUGGGAAGGAGAAAUGUGAAACCCGGCAGCGGCCGACCUAGGCGGUCUUGUGGCCCGGAGCCGGCCCGGCCCGAAAACCAUAGACCUGGUUGUACUGUAGCUUGUUGUUUGGGGGACCAAAUUUUCUAGAGAGAACUAGAGCACUUUUGUUGUGUUUUUUUGUUUUGUUUUUGUUUUUUGCCUUGUCGAUUCCCGAAUAAAUUUUGUGUUCCUUCUUUUAA